GUCUCCCCCGCGCAAAAAAAAAAAAAAAAAAGAAAUUUCAUGAAGUCGUUUUCUCAACGUUAAAUUACCGUGUACCACUUUCGGGAUUUUUGCCUAAUGGCAGUACUGCUUGAACUUUUGAUUACUAGAUGUGUUUUUUUGUAUAGCUAUGUCCCAUUUAAAAAUUAAAUUAAUUUCCUUGAAACAAAAUCCUUAUGGUGAAUGGGAAGCCAGUGCCACUUGCCACAAAUGGCUUAUGGAAGAAGAACCAGUGUCAGAUUUCGCAGUUCAGGAAUGACUUUAGACAAUAUCAGUCGGGCAGCUGUGGAUCGAAUAAUCCGGGUGGAUCAUGCAGGCGAAUAUGGAGCAAACCGCAUCUAUGCCGGGCAGAUGGCUGUCCUGGGUCGGACCAGCGUCGGGCCAGUCAUUCAGAAAAUGUGGGAUCAAGAAAAGGACCAUUUGAAAAAGUUCAAUGAGUUGAUGGUUACGUUCAGGGUCCGGCCAACAGUUCUGAUGCCCUUGUGGAACGUGCUGGGGUUUGCACUGGGGGCGGGGACCGCCUUGCUCGGGAAGGAAGGUGCCAUGGCCUGCACCGUGGCGGUGGAAGAGAGCAUAGCACAUCACUACAACAACCAGAUCAGGACGCUGAUGGAGGAGGACCCUGAAAAAUACGAGGAACUUCUUCAGCUGAUAAAGAAAUUUCGGGAUGAAGAGCUUGAGCACCAUGACAUAGGCCUCGACCAUGAUGCAGAAUUGGCUCCAGCCUAUGCCGUCCUGAAGAGCAUUAUCCAGGCCGGAUGCAGAGUGGCGAUAUAUUUAUCAGAAAGAUUAUAAAGUGUGUCCAGUUUUGCCUGUCUAUAAAAGAUGAUAGUAAUUUACCAAGUGACAUUUGCAGAGAAACAGGUGUACAGUUAUCGUUGUACUUUUGUACAAUGUGAAUUUUGUUAAUAAAUUAUAAGGUUUGUUUUUUUUUUUUUAAACUCUGCAGUGUUGAUUUUUCUCUGGGUUGUUUUUUCUGCCAUGAGACCAACAGGUCACCAGCCUUGUUCAAGUUACAGCAAACGAAGCUGGGCCUUGUUUGGUCUCAUACUUAAUUUUCUUUUAUAUACAUGUUUUUCUUUUACAUGCAUAUAUAUAUAUUUUAUUUUAUUUUAUGUUUUUUGGAGACAGGGCCUCGCUCUUUUGUCCAGGCCGGGUCACAACUCACUGCAGCCUGGACCUCCUAGCCUCAAGCAAUCCACCCACCUCAGCCUUCCAAGUAGCUGGGACUACAGGUGUGCACCACCACAGCUGGCUAAUUCUAUUUUUUUAUAGAGGCGAAGUCUCACUAUGUCGCCAGGCUGGUCUCUAACUCCUGGGCUCAGUGAUCCUCCCGUUUCGACUUCCCAAAGUGCUGGGAUUACAGGUGUGAGCCACUUCACCAGGCCCAUUUUCUCCUAAAACUUCAAGGACAAAUCAUUAAUAAUGUAACAGGAAUCUUUAGGAGAAAAAACAAUUUGGUUUACUGAUAACAAAAGAUAAUUGGAAACAUGAGAGUAUUUGAGAUUGGCCAAGCAGAACUAUGAAGUCCAUCAAAAUUCAUACGAUGAAAUCUUCACUCUCAAGUUGAUAGAAGGUGGGGCCCUUGGGAAGUGUGAGGUCAUGAGAGUGGAGCCCUCAUGAAUGGGAUCAGUGCCUUAUGAAAGGCCCUAGAGAGAUACCUCAUCCUCUCCACAGUGUGAGACUUCAAGGGGAAGUAUGAGACUUCUCUGAGGAAGCAGACCCUUCACAAGCAAAAUCAGCCAGCACUUUGAUCACGGACUUCCCAGCCUCUAGGACUGUGAGCAAUAAAUGUUUGAUGUUUAUAAGCCACCCAGACUGUGGUAUUUUGUUAUAGCAGCCUGAACAGACUAAGACGGGGGUGUUGCUUCCAUCAAAGGAUGUACUAAGUUGUGGAUUAUUUGUGAAAUUGAAUUACAACCUUUUCCUUAAGGUCUUUUACCACCUCCCCCCCAAAAAAAUCCCCCAAAACUGAUUCAGAUUUUCAUACUUUAAUGAAAUAUUUUAUAAUUUGCAAAUUUUUAAGUAAUUUAUGAAAAACCUAGAUCAGUGGAUCUCCUCUCUGGCUGCCCAUUAGAAUGUCCUGUGGAGAUUAAACUUUUUUUUUUCAGUUUAUGGACCAAGAGUUUUGAUUUAUUUAGGGUGGAGUUCAGGAUCAGAAUGGUUUCAGAAGCUCCCAGGUGAUUCCGGAGUGAGUUGGAGCUGCAAGCCCCUGAGCUAGAUUAUAAGAUGCUUCUGGGAAAGAACCACAUUUUAGGAAUUUGCUUCCCACCCAGUGCCCUGCAUUUAAUCAGCACCUGAUGACUUGGCAGGACUUGCCCCACCAGGGUCUGGCUUUGAAGGGUAGUGGACACCAGGAUCCUUUGGAUUAAUCCUCUGCCACCUCUCUCUUUUCCUCAACCGAGAGUGAAUUUAUGUAAUUGAGUGAAAGUCUACGAAUCAUAAUUGUAAUAAAUUAAGGCUGGGCAUUUGUUUGAAAUUAGAUAGGAUAAAGCCAAAGGUUUGAACAAGUUGUGGAUGGUUUGUAAAAAUUAAUCUUACAAAAUAAAUGCUGUGUGUGAACACGUUGAUUAAAUUCAAAAGGGUAUUAUUUGGUUUUUCUGUAAAUUGAACCUUGAAAUAAAAGCACAACAAGGUUUUCUUAAGGUACUGAUCUGCUCUUUAACAAGAAUUUGUAAAGGGUUAUAAAAGGUUUACAAGAAUCUCACCUCAUGGUCAAACUAGUUAAGAUUGGAUAGAUUUAUCUAUAAGGUAUUAUUAAAAAUUGGGGAUGACAUUAAUAGUAGACUGAUGCAAGGAUGACAUUUGACUCUGUCUUGAACAAGAUUUUUAUGUAAUAGUAAAGGAUAAUGAAAGAUUUUUGUUUGCCUUGCAAAUAAACUACCAAAAAAAGAAGGGAAAGGCAAGAGACAAAUUGUUUGGAAAGUUGUCUUCCCUUUUAAUGGGUAAAGGUUUUGUGCUUUUUAAAAAAGUUUUUGAGUCAUCAUUUUGGCUAAUGAUAACCUGGAAUUCUAUUUUAUAAUAUCAAGUGUUUUAAACCUUUAAUAUGUUCAGUAGGCUUCCCCAAAUCGAACUUUAGCUUCAAGAUUGUCUUUUUUGACCCCUAACUUUUGGAUGCCAUAGAGGGCCCCUGGAUUAUUUGACAUGUUUAAUUACAUGGGAUUGCCAAAAUAAGAAUAAUGUUUAAUCUUAUUCAGGUUACAUUUUAGUGAAUAACAUUAAUAUAUAUAUUAAUAUAUGUUCCAAAAUUGUAUAAGAUUUCUAAAAUUCUAAUAUCUGAGUAUAUGAUAUCAAUUAUAAUUAGGGUUAUUAUGUUAAGUUAUUGUAAACCACAGAAAUAACGAAAUUUCUUUGUCAAUUGUGUUUUUGACUGUGACUGUCUAAAGACAUCUUGUGAUUCACAGACAAUCGUAGUCUUGUUUUGAUCCUCUUCAAAAGGUGGUUUAUAAUCAGCUGUAGAACUUAGGUGCUCUUAAAUGCAUAUUUCCAAUAUCUUUAGAUUGUGAUAUUAGAAUAAAGGAAAAACAUUCAGGACUCAUGAAGAGCUGAAAUAUUCAUGAAUAUCAAGCAGAGCAAGAGUUAACUGAAUGGGCUGAACUAAUAGAAGACAUGUAAUCUGUUUAACUUUUUGCUUAAAACUUUGCUGAUGUUUUGUUUUUCAGAGUCAAGAAAACUUUUAUUUUGAGCUAUUUACAGCUUUUAACAAUUGAGUAAGGUAUACUCCUGUGAACAAAAUUUGGAGUGUAUUUGUUCCUCUGCUGGUUUCUCUAGAAUUCAGAAACUAUUUGUGAGUAUUCUUAUGGCAAUGUAGUUAUUUGCAUAAGUGCAACAAGAAUCCAUUUUCUUUUGCAACAGGACACAAUUGGAGAAACUGGUGGUUUUACCAGUUUCUGAUAGAAGGGUGUGCUUCCCUUUAAGGAAUCAAGCUUGACUUGCAGAGCCAAAAAAAAGGAGAAACUGGCCUCAUACCUUGUCUACACAGUCCUUGUACAGGGCUCCUAACCUGUGAUGAGUAAAGAAUGUCACUUUCUAACAGGUCCAGGAGCCCCAAGUUAUCUUGGGACCUCAAGAAGAGAGGAAUUUACCCAACUCAUAGGUAUUGGAGGGUACAAACCCAUUGCUGGGCUUGACUUUAAAAAGUCUUUUCUGAUAUUCCUUAUGGAACAGAAUUCCAUCAGAGCCAAUUUUAAAAGCAUAUGUGAAAAAUAAUUAUUCUUGCUGUACUUUAUGCAAAUAAUCAGGCCAAGUAUAAGACUAAAGUUUAUUUUGCAAACAAUCCUAUUAUGAUUUGUUUUUAACAAAAAUGAAGACUGGAGAGUUUCAAAACUUAUCACACUUGUCAUUAAAUUCUAGUUUUAUUAGUUGUUUUUAAGUUUUUGUCUGUAUUUUAGACUAACCCUACUUAUUCUGUGAACCAACCAGUGAUCUCUGGCUGAAGCUCAGAAGAAACAAGGGAUGGUUAAUAUAGAAAUCUGGAUCUGGAUCAAUAUUCUAGAGGAGGCGGAGGUUGCCGUGAGUUGAGAUCAUGCCAUUUUACUCCAGCCUGGGCAACAAGAGUGAAACUCCAUCCCAAAAAAAAAGAAAAAAAGAAAACAUGUUCAAACCAAUCCUUGUACAUGAAUGCUCAUAAUAACUAAAAGUGGAAACAACUCAUGUCCAUCAACUGAUGAACAAAAUGGCAAUAUACCCAAACAAGGCAAUCUUACUCAGCUAUAAAAAGGAAUAAAGUAGUGAUACAUGAUACAA